CUUUUCCGCCCGCUCCCCCCUCCCCCCGAGCGCCGCUCCGGCUGCACCGCGCUCGCUCCGAGUUUCAGGCUCGUGCUAAGCUAGCGCCGUCGUCGUCUCCCUUCAGUCGCCAUCAUGAUUAUCUACCGGGACCUCAUCAGCCACGAUGAGAUGUUCUCCGACAUCUACAAGAUCCGGGAGAUCGCGGACGGGUUGUGCCUGGAGGUGGAGGGGAAGAUGGUCAGUAGGACAGAAGGUAACAUUGAUGACUCGCUCAUUGGUGGAAAUGCCUCCGCUGAAGGCCCCGAGGGCGAAGGUACCGAAAGCACAGUAAUCACUGGUGUCGAUAUUGUCAUGAACCAUCACCUGCAGGAAACAAGUUUCACAAAAGAAGCCUACAAGAAGUACAUCAAAGAUUACAUGAAAUCAAUCAAAGGGAAACUUGAAGAACAGAGACCAGAAAGAGUAAAACCUUUUAUGACAGGGGCUGCAGAACAAAUCAAGCACAUCCUUGCUAAUUUCAAAAACUACCAGUUCUUUAUUGGUGAAAACAUGAAUCCAGAUGGCAUGGUUGCUCUAUUGGACUACCGUGAGGAUGGUGUGACCCCAUAUAUGAUUUUCUUUAAGGAUGGUUUAGAAAUGGAAAAAUGUGAUGCAAAAGAAAGAAAUCCCUGCGCUUUCUGUCUGUCUUUGUGGCGGCCCAGAUUGAAUUGGGGAAUACAUCUUUAGCCUGGAAAUGUAGGCUGCAUGUUAAUGGUAAUGUAACUUUUGCAGUGUAAUGUUUGAAAAAUAUUAAUGUAGUUUUUGCUUUUACAGUAACAAAUGUGGCAAUUAUUUUGGAUCUAUCACCUGUCAUCAUAACUGGCUUCUGCUUGUCAUCCACACAACACCAGGACUUAAGACAAAUGGGACUGAUGUCAUCUUGAGCUCUUCAUUUAUUUUGACUGUGAUUUAUUUGGAGUGGAGGCAUUGUUUUUAAGAAAAACAUGUCAUGUAGGUUGUCUAAAAAUAAAAUGCAUUUAAACUCAUUUGAGAGAAUGCCUUUUAGUUUAAUGCAUAUUUAAACUAAAUUGAUCCUGUAGUGUUCCUGGAGAAGCUAGAGCCUGAUUGUAGGCUACUACUCAUCAAUUAACUUCUACAGUGGAGACUACUUCUGGGACUGGAAUAUAAAAAAGAAUCAAAGGUUCUGAUUUUGAGUUGCAAUAAAGGGAAAGACCAUGCUCAUAGCAGUGCCAACAUCUGAAGUGUGGAGCCUUACCCAUUUCAUCACCUACAACGGAAGUAGUUAACUGGAAGAGAUUACCAAGAGAAUAAAAAGAGACUCAUUCAGUGGAAGCAACUUUGUCUCAGCUUAUUUCACAUAAAGAGAGCGAAGUCUUUUGGGAUGAAUGUUAAUUAAACUCCCUGGUAACUAGAACAGGGACUGGCAAACUAGCCUAUCUGACCACCUGUUUUGUACACUUUAAGGUGGUUGGUUGCCUUUUUAAAUGGUUGAGGGGAAAAGAAUACCUUGUGGGAUAUGGAAUUUAAGUUCGAGUCCAGUUUUAUUGGAACGUGGCUAUGCUUAUUCAUUUAUGGAUUGACUGUGGCUGUUGUCAGUGCAUGAGCAGAGUUGUGUCUAACAGACUAGAGCCUGCAAGUUUGCCAGCCCCUGAUUUAAAAGAUGAAGGUACACAGAAUGUGGGCUGGCUGGUGGGCAAAGGGGUAAAAAUGUUCUCUAUAUUGUAUCUGAAAAGAUGGGGUGUCUGAAUAAGAAAAUGCAUCUAUUUGACAGACCUGGAGCAGUUGCUAUCUGCUGCUAUGGUUUCCACCACAGAUGCAAGAAGAACAUGUCCUUGCGCUUUCCGUCUGUCUAAUUGUGGCAGCUGAGAUUGAAUAGAGGAAUACAGGAGGAAAAAAAGCGGGAAGAGUUUUUGAGGCAGGUCGGUCACCCAGGCUUGUAGUGCAGUGGCACAAGCAACUCACUGCAUUCUCUGCAUCCUGUGCUCAAGCCAUUUUCCCACCUCAGUCUCACUAGUUGCUGGGACUGCAGGCAUGCACCCCUAUGCCCAGCUAAUUUUUGUAGAGACCGAGUAUCGCUUAGUUGCCCAGGGUGGUCUCAACUCCUGGGCUCAAGGAGAUCUGCCCACCUCAGCCUCCCAAAGUGCAGGCCUAGCCUGGGAGGGGAAUUUUCAAAACGUGAGUUUUGGGAAAUAGUCUAUCAGCCUUACCUGGUUGAUUACACUUGUAAAAGAAAGAUUAAAAGCAGGCCAGUGACUCUGGUCUGCUUGAACAUGUGAAUGUAGUGGUUUGAGCAAUCUGGAGUUUGCCCUAGUGUCAAAUUCCAGACUGUCCAUAGUGUCCAAAACCUGAGGCAGAUACUAAUGUUAACCCCCAGCACCCCGUGAUUGGAAACAAACCUAAAUACGUAUUGGGAACUUAAUAGCAAUUUUAAGCAUUCUGAUAGAUUUUUUGUAGGGAUGGGGUCAUGCCAUGUGGCCCAGGCUGGUCUGAAAACUCUGGCCUCAAGUGAUCUCAAGCUUUGGCCUUCUAAAGUGUUGGGAUUACAGGUGUGAGGCAUUGCACCUGGCUUAGCGUUCUGAUUUGACAUUGUAAUGAAAAGUGUGAGUCUCAUCUACAGGGCCUUUUGUCCUCUGAAAUGAUAGCAGGAAGGGAAUUUUCAGGCAGUGGUCAAAGCUGGGGAAACCAGGAUAGUGAAGAAGGCCUUGAGGUGAGAGAUGGAAGCUAAUUGGUGAACUAGCCUUGGAAGCCUGAAACAGACAAGUAGCAAUUCAGAGACUUUGUGGGCUCCACUGCUCCAACUUGUUUUGAAGAUUUUCAGUUCUGCAGAAGAGGUAUUUCCCCAGUUGUCCUUUCAGUGCUCUUAGCUGUUUUCCCAACAUCCAGAUCCAAUCAAGGCUGGGACAUAGCAUUUUAUCAUGUCUAUUUAAGUCAGAAGUGAUGAACCCCAGCUGUUUACCUCAUGGUAAACCUUUGAAGAUUCCAGGUAGAAUCUUCUCAGACUUUGAAGACUGUCUCAUUUUAUAUCUUUUUCUCGUUAUUCCUAGGGUCAAGACGUUUUGGGCAAGAAUAAGGAUGUGAACAUCAGAAAGCUCAUAACAUUUUGUUUUUGAUGCUAAGUUUAACAAAGGCAUGCUUUAGUAGCCUGUGGGCCCUAGGGUUUGUUAAAGUGUGGAGAACAACUGAGUGGAGCAAGAGGACUUUUCUAGGAAGGUCCUUGUAAUGUGACAUUUGAAAACAAAUGAAGGUGUGGAAGUAGGCCAUGUGGAUAUCAGGACAAACCAUUCCAGGCCAAGACAACAGCAGUUAGUCUGGAGUGUGAUGUGUUCUGGGAAAAAAGUGGCCACUUUGCUAACCCAAGAAGACAGGAAGGGUUGUAAAGCAGUGGGAGUGUGCAAGGAAGGAAGACCAGACCUCAAGGAAACCACAGGCGCUCUGAGCAGAAGAGUUACAUGAUAUGACUCAAAUUUUUAAAGGAUCACUUUGGCUGCCAGGUGGCAGGGUAAAAGCAUAGAAUAAUUGUGUAUAAUGUGUUUUUAAGGCAAAGAUAGUGGCUUAGUCUAGGGUAGUAGACUGAGGUGGUAGGAAAUGAAGAUAGAGACAACAGGAUAUGCUGGUGGGUGAGGAUGGAUUUAAUGUUGAUACAAGUAUUUUGGUCUGAGCGUUUGGAAGAAAGUUGGCACUGAGGUGGGAAGUCGAGUUUAGUUUUGUUAGUUUUGGAUGUGUUAAGUUUGAGAUGCUGAUUCUUCAGAGAAGUCUAAGCUGGAGAACUAUAUAGAGAGUGGAAAGAUAACAAUAGACAUUGAAAGCCAUGAUACAGGAUAAGGUCAUUUGGAGAGAGGAUAGACUGCAUUCCAACAUGAGAUUGGUUGACAAAGAGAAACCAACAAAGGUAAUUAAGAGGUGCUCCCACUGCACUUGUACUCAGAAGGCUGAGGUAGGAUUGUUAGAGGCCAGCCUGGGCACCACAGGGAGACCCCAUCUCUAAAAUUUAGCCAGGAACCAUGGCUCAUGCCUGUAGCCCCAGGAAUUUGGGAGGCUGAGUGGGGAGGAUCGCUUGAGGUCAGGAGUUUGAGACCAGCCUGGGCAACAUAGGGAGACCUAAAAAAAUUAAUUGGGCAUCUGUAGUCCCAGCUACUCAGGCGGCUGAGCUGAGAGGAUGGCUUGAGUCCGAGAGAUUGAGGGUGCAGUGAGCUGUGAUCAUACCACUGCACUCCAGCCUGGGCGGCAGUGAGACACUAUCUGAAAAAAGUUUAAAAAUUUUAAAAAAGAAGGAACUGCCCCUGAGGUAAGAACCAAGGGAGGGCCUCCCAGAGGUCAGGUGGAAAAAGUUUUAGGAAGGAGGAAGUAGUCAACAGGGUUACCUGUUGCAAAGUACUUAAGUAAUAUGAGGCCUGAUAGUGGUAAACUUGACUACCGUUGGAUUUCACUAGUGGGAAAGGAAGUCUAAUUAAAAUGCACUCAAGAGACUAACAGUCGCAGGCAUGAAAUACAAUACAGGUACAUGGUUUUUUAUUAUGUGUGCAUCUGCUUCAGUAAUAGGUGUGAAUUACUCAUUUGGAUCAUUAGGAGUUUCAAAAUCUAGUUAAAUGACUAGAUUUUUGUUGAUGUAAAUUCUGUCAUUCUGAACUGCAGGGAUUGUCAGUAACUUAACUGCAAACUAAACUGGUGAUAAUUAUGGUAAAAUUGCAAGACGAGCAAUAAAUCUCAACCAACUUGAGAGAACACUGAUAA